AUAUUGGAUGCCGCAGCCGCUGCUGCCAGCGCUUCCUCCUCUGUCUUCGCCGAGCGGGGCUGGUUCCUGCGGCCCGAGCGGCGGGGAGGUGAAACAGGAGCCCGUCGGAGGAAGGGGCAGAAGGGAGUGGAGAGUGUAGGGGAAGGGGCUAGAGGGAGGGGGACCGAAACGGAGCGGGGCAGAGAAGAGAAGGCGCCGCGGCCCAGCCCCUCCCCCGCCCGCCGCCGACCCGCCCCGGCAGCGCCUCUGUUCCCUAGAACGGCGCUCCCCCCGCCCUAGCGGCCAUGCCGGUGCCGCUCUGCCGCUGAGGGAGCCCUUCCCCGCCAGCGCGUGCCCUUCCACUCCGCCCCGAGGUCGCAGCGGCCCGCUCUCCCGCCAGCGCCCCCUCCUCGCGGCCACGCAGCAGCCCGCGUCUCGCUCUCCCCACCCAGUGCAGUGGCCGCCGCCUCUUCCGCCGCCGGGCUCGGGGCCUCCGCAGCGACAACAUGGAGGCCGUGAAGACCUUCAAUAGCGAGUUGUAUUCCCUGAAUGACUAUAAACCACCCAUUUCGAAAGCGAAAAUGACCCAAAUUACUAAGGCAGCCAUCAAAGCUAUUAAGUUCUAUAAACAUGUGGUACAGAGUGUUGAGAAGUUUAUUCAGAAAUGUAAACCAGAAUACAAAGUACCUGGACUUUAUGUUAUUGACUCCAUUGUGCGACAAUCCCGACAUCAGUUUGGUCAAGAAAAGGAUGUGUUUGCACCCAGAUUUAGUAAUAACAUCAUUAGCACUUUCCAGAAUUUAUAUCGUUGCCCUGGGGAUGACAAGAGUAAAAUAGUGAGAGUACUAAACUUAUGGCAGAAGAAUAAUGUAUUUAAGAGUGAGAUUAUUCAGCCCCUUUUGGAUAUGGCAGCCGGGAUUCCGCCUCCAGUUGUCACACCUGUUUUGGCCAGCACUACCACUGCUAUGAGCAAUACUCCAGGAACUCCUGUGACACCUGUUACUCCGGCCAAUGUGGUCCAAGGCUUACCUGAUCCGUGGGUAUCUCAGAUAACAAAUACAGAUACACUUGCGGCUGUAGCUCAGAUCUUGCAAAGUCCUCAAGGCCAGCAGCUUCAACAAUUAAUACAAACCUUACAGAUACAACAACAGAAGCCCCAGCCUUCCAUUCUGCAGGCCCUAGAUGCUGGUCUUGUUGUUCAGUUGCAAGCUCUUACGGCACAACUUACAGCUGCAGCUGCAGCUGCCAACACUCUUACUCCCUUAGAACAGGGAGUCUCCUUUAACAAGAAGUUGAUGGAUAGGUUUGAUUUUGGGGAAGACUCUGAGCAUAGUGAAGAACCCAAAAAGGAAAUUCCAGCUUCACAACUUUCUCACGUUUCAGAAUCUGUGAACAAUUCCAUUUUUCAUCAGAUAGCAGAACAACUACAACAGCAAAACCUAGAACAUCUCAGACAGCAGCUCUUGGAGCAGCAACAGCCUCAAAAGGCCACUCCUCAGGAUAGUCAGGAAGGAACCUUUGGGUCAGAGCAUUCAGCGUCACCAUCACAAGGGAGUAGUCAGCAGCAUUUUCUUGAACCUGAAGUCAAUUUGGAUGAUUCCAUAGAUAUUCAGCAACAGGAUAUGGAUAUAGAUGAAGGGCAAGAUGGAGUGGAAGAGGAGGUCUUUGAACAAGAAGCUAAGAAAGUGGCGGUUCGCUCAAGAUCAAGAACACAUUCACGAUCUCGUUCAAGAUCACCAAGAAAACGAAGGUCUAGGUCACGGUCUGGCUCUAGAAAGCGUAAACACAGAAAGCGAUCACGCUCCCGCUCAAGAGAAAGAAAGAGGAAAUCAUCACGGUCGUAUUCAAGUGAAAGGAGAGCCAGAGAAAGGGAGAAAGAACGACAGAAAAAGGGAUUACCUCCAAUUAGAUCUAAAACACUAAGUGUAUGUAGUACUACUCUCUGGGUUGGGCAAGUGGACAAGAAGGCAACACAGCAAGACUUAACCAACCUGUUUGAAGAGUUUGGACAGAUUGAAUCCAUUAAUAUGAUUCCUCCCCGGGGCUGUGCUUAUGUCUGCAUGGUUCAUCGACAAGAUGCAUUUCGAGCUCUUCAGAAACUCAGUUCUGGAUCAUAUAAAAUUGGGUCCAAGGUCAUUAAGAUCGCUUGGGCUUUAAACAAAGGUGUAAAAACAGAAUACAAACAAUUCUGGGAUGUGGAUCUUGGAGUUACAUAUAUACCAUGGGAAAAAGUUAAAGUGGAUGACUUGGAAGGUUUUGCAGAAGGAGGCAUGAUUGAUCAGGAGACUGUAAAUACUGAGUGGGAAACUGUGAAAAGCUCAGAACCUGUUAAAGAGACGGUCCAGACAACUCAGAGCCCAACUCCAGUUGAAAAGGAGACAGUGGUCACAACCCAGGCAGAGGUUUUCCCUCCUCCUGUUGCUAUGUUGCAGAUUCCAGUGGCGCCAGCCGUGCCUACAGUUAGUUUAGUCCCACCAGCAUUUCCUGUGUCGAUGCCGGUUCCUCCUCCUGGAUUCAGUCCAAUCCCUCCACCUCCUUUUUUAAGAGCAAGUUUUAACCCUUCACAACCACCACCUGGUUUCAUGCCGCCUCCAGUUCCCCCACCUGUUGUGCCACCCCCUACGAUUCCACCAGUAGUACCAACAUCUUUAGUGCAGCCGUCAUUAUCCAUGACACCGGAAACUGUGAAAGAUGUUGGAUUUGGUAGCCUUGUUAUACCAGGCGGUUCUGUUGCCAGCAAUCUUGCUACUUCCGCUCUGCCAGCUGGAAAUGUUUUUAAUGCUCCAACUAAACAGGCAGAGCCUGAAGAAAAAGUACCUCAUCUUAUAGACCACCAGAUUUCUUCUGGUGAAAACACCAGAUCAGUGAUUCCAAAUGAUAUUUCAAGUAAUGCUGCAAUUUUAGGAGGACAGCCGCCAAAUGUGACAAGCAAUUCUGGAAUUCUGGGAGUCCAAAGACCAAAUGUAUCAAGUAAUUCUGAAAUUCUUGGGGUCCGGCCAUCUAAUGUUUCCAGUAGUUCUGGGAUUAUUGCAGCCCAACCACCAAAUAUUCUAAAUAACUCUGGAAUAUUGGGAAUACAGCCACCCAGUGUGUCAAAUAGUUCUGGACUUUUGGGAGUGCUACCCCCAAAUAUACCUAACAAUUCUGGACUUGUAGGAGUACAGCCACCAAAUGUUCCAAAUACUCCUGGACUUCUGGGAACACAGCCACCAGCUGGACCUCAAAACUUACCCCCUUUAAGUAUCCCUAAUCAAAGGAUGCCCACAAUGCCAAUGUUAGACAUUCGUCCGGGACUAAUACCACAGGCACCUGGGCCAAGAUUCCCUUUAAUACAGCCUGGAAUUCCACCCCAACGGGGAAUCCCACCCCCAUCGGUACUUGAUUCAGCUCUUCAUCCACCACCCCGUGGACCUUUUCCUCCAGGAGAUAUUUUUAGUCAACCAGAAAGACCUUUUUUAGCUCCUGGAAGACAAAGCGUAGACAAUGUUACUAACCCAGAAAAAAGGAUACCACUUGGGAAUGAUAACAUUCAACAGGAAGGAGAUAGAGAUUACCGGUUUCCUCCUAUAGAAACCAGGGAAAGCAUUAGUAGACCUCCCCCUGUGGAUGUUAGAGAUGUGGUUGGGCGGCCUAUAGAUCCAAGAGAAGGUCCUGGACGGCCUCCACUAGAUGGUAGGGAUCAUUUUGGAAGACCUCCUGUAGAUAUAAGAGAGAAUCUUGUGAGGCCAGGUAUAGAUCAUCUUGGUCGAAGAGACCACUUUGGCUUUAAUCCAGAGAAGCCCUGGGGGCAUAGAGGAGAUUUUGAUGAGAGAGAGCAUCGGGUUCUACCGGUCUAUGGUGGUCCAAAAGGCUUACAUGAAGAAAGAGGUAGAUUUCGGUCUGGAAACUAUCGAUUUGAUCCUAGAAGUGGUCCUUGGAACCGAGGAUUUGGACAAGAAGUUCACAGAGAUUUUGAUGACCGCAGAAGACCCUGGGAGAGGCAAAGGGAUAGGGAUGACAGAGAUUUUGAUUUCUGCAGAGAAAUGAAUGGAAAUCGUCUUGGACGAGACAGAAUUCAAAACACUUGGGUUCCCCCUCCUCAUGCUCGGGUUUUUGAUUAUUUUGAAGGGGCCACUUCUCAACGAAAAGGUGAUAAUGUGCCUCAGGUUAAUGGUGAAAAUACAGAGAGACAUGCUCAGCCACCACCUAUACCAGUACAGAAUGAUCCUGAACUUUAUGAAAAACUGACAUCUUCAAAUGAAAUAAACAAGGAGAAGAGUGACACAGUUGCUGAUAUAGAAAGUGAACCAGUGGUAGAAAGCACAGAAACUGAGGGGACAUAAUCAUCACUCAGUAGGUAAAAGAUACCUUUUGUAAAGUUGUCAUCUCUCUGUAAUAGAUAAUGGCUGACUGGACCAUAGUUGUUCACUUUUGUCUGCCAGAAUUAAGUUAAUCUGAUGUUCAUGUUCACCUUUCUCUUAAAAUAAUUGUACAACUGACUUGUAUAGACAUUGUUCUUAAUAUGAACAUGGUAGGUAAACUUUUUUUUUAUUUUUUUCUGAUAAAAUACAAAUGUUGGCCCCAGAUUCUUUUAACGUCAAGGAAAUGAAUAACAGCUUGUCAGAGACUUCCUAUGGAAGAAAGAAUUUUUUAGAUACUAUCAUUAGGUUGGAUAUGGUAAUAGAUAUAUUUCAGAAUAGCAAGUGGUGGUAUAUCUUAUCCAUAUCUUUAGGCUGCUGCAGAAUUUUAAGGUUAUAGAUAAAGCUGUGAUAUUUUAUGCAAAGACUGGCUCUAGGUAUUUGAGGAGCACAAUACAGAGAUUUUAAAAAGUGAUUUUGUAAAAUCUACACUACGGUCUCUGUUUCUCCAAAGUAAGUGUUUGUGAUUUGUUCCUCAUACUGCAGUGAGUAAAAAAGAAACAAGAAAACAACAACAUAAAUAUUAAAGUACGUUUCAAUGUUGGGUGAAUUUUGUUUUUAGAUGCCAAUAAAACUUAUUUGUUUGAUAACAGUGUUCUAGGAAUUGUAUUUUUUUAACCUAUAAAUUCUUAAAACCUUGAAUUAUUAUUAGCAUGUGCUUAUUUUUUGCAAAAGCUUUCUAUCAUAACAACAAUGAACUAUGUGGUGGAAAAAGCAUGUACUUUGAUAUAAAAAUCAUGCAGCCUCCUCA